AUGCAGAGGUCACCACCACGCAGCAGAGACAGGCGUCCUGUGGGCGAUGCAGAGGUCACCACCACGCAGCAGAGACGGGCGUCCCCACAGGCAGUGCAGAGGUCACCACCACACAGCAGAGACAGGCGUCCCCACGGGCAGUGCAGAGGUCACCACCACGCAGCAGAGACAGGCGUCCCCACGGGCAGUGCAGAGGUCACCACCACACAGCAGAGACAGGCGUCCUGUGGGCAGUGCAGAGGUCACCACCACGCAGCAGAGACAGGCGUCCUGUGGGCAGUGCAGAGGUCACCACCACGCAGCAGAGACGGGCGUCCCCACAGGCAGUGCAGAGGUCACCACCACACAGCAGAGACAGGAGUCCUGUGGGCAGUGCAGAGGUCACCACCACGCAGCAGAGACAGGCGUCCUGUGGGCAGUGCAGAGGUCACCACCACGCAGCAGAGACAGGCGUCCUGUGGGCAGUGCAGAGGUCACCACCACGCAGCAGAGACGGGCGUCCCCACAGGCAGUGCAGAGGUCACCACCACACAGCAGAGACAGGAGUCCUGUGGGCAGUGCAGAGGUCACCACCACGCAGCAGAGACGGGCGUCCCCACAGGCAGUGCAGAGGUCACCACCACACAGCAGAGACAGGCGUCCCCACAGGCAGUGCAGAGGUCACCACCACGCAGCAGAGACAGGCGUCCCCACGGGCAGUGCAGAGGUCACCACCACACAGCAGAGACAGGCAUCCUGUGGGCAGUGCAGAGGUCACCACCACGCAGCAGAGACAGGCGUCCUGUGGGCAGUGCAGAGGUCACCACCACGCAGCAGAGACGGGCGUCCCCACAGGCAGUGCAGAGGUCACCACCACACAGCAGAGACAGGAGUCCUGUGGGCAGUGCAGAGGUCACCACCACGCAGCAGAGACAGGCGUCCUGUGGGCAGUGCAGAGGUCACCACCACGCAGCAGAGACGGGCGUCCCCACAGGCAGUGCAGAGGUCACCCCACACAGCAGAGACAGGCGUCCUGUGGGCGAUGCAGAGGUCACCACCACGCAGCAGAGACGGGCGUCCCCACAGGCAGUGCAGAGGUCACCACACUGA